GUUGCUGGCUUUUUCAGGAGCUGCUCGCUCGCAGCCAGAGACGCUGCUUUUUUUUUCCGGGUUCGGAGCCGUUCCGGAUGCUUUAGGCUGCCGGAUGUCUGAUCUCCGAAUAACUGAGGCGUUUCUGUACAUGGAUUAUCUGUGUUUUAGAGCACUUUGCUGCAAGGGACCACCACCUGCACGACCAGAAUAUGACCUGGUUUGCAUAGGCCUCACAGGUUCUGGCAAAACCAGUCUGUUGUCCAAACUCUGCAGUGAAAGCCCCGAUAACGUCGUGUCGACCACAGGUUUUAGUAUUAAAGCAGUGCCAUUCCAGAAUGCCAUCUUGAAUGUAAAAGAACUUGGAGGGGCUGAUAACAUCCGGAAAUACUGGAGCCGCUACUACCAAGGAUCUCAAGGGGUAAUAUUUGUAUUAGACAGUGCCUCUUCAGAGGAUGAUUUAGAAGCUGCUAGAAAUGAGCUGCACUCAGCUCUUCAGCAUCCACAGUUAUGCACUUUACCCUUUUUAAUAUUGGCCAAUCAUCAAGACAAGCCAGCAGCUCGCUCAGUACAAGAGGGGCCUUCCAGAGAACAAAUGGCUGGUCCUUUUCCAAGGGGACAGAUUUUCCUACCUGAUGCUUUUGUUCUCCAGCAAGAAAAGAAAAUGAAAACUGUUGUCUUCCCCUAGAAUAUUGAGUCCAGAGUAAGCUGAAGCUUUGUGUAUUUCUUUUGUAGUGAUUUCCUUCAUAUAUAUAUGAAUAGAGUGACUACUGAAUAUCGGAGGUUUGGGCUAGAGGUAAAACCAUCUCUUUGAUAUGCAGAGCAAAAUGAAAUGAUAAAACAUCAAAUGUUGGGAUGUUUGAAAGAGUUUCCUACAUGACCUGUCAGGUCUUAAUUUGCUCAGAGUAAUGCCUUGGGCCUUCUUGUGUUGUUAAUAGCCUUUAGGGGAAAUUAUGUUGGAGGCUGUAUCAAUCAUCUGGCCUUUUUCUUGUUUCAUACAAGAUUCCCUGUACCCUUAUCUUUCUAUCAGAAUAUUCUAGAUUAGCUGUGUAUUUGCUGGGCAGCCUUAGUACUGAUGCCUUAAAAGAACAUGUCACCUGCCCCUGUCUUACUAGGCACUUUCCAAAUAAUAAUAAUAAUACUUUGUGUUCUGAAACCUAAUUUUCUUUCUUUCUUUCCCCCCAACUUUUAUUUUAGGUUUAGGGGGUUACAUGUGCAGGUUGUUUUCCCUGCAGCAGGUAAAUUGUGUCACUGGGGUUUGGUGUACAAAUCAUUUUGUCACCCAGGUAGUAAAUAUCAUACCCAAUUGGUACUUCAAAUCUCUCCCUCCUCCCACCCUCCAUCCUCAAGUAAGCCCUGGUGUCUAUCGUGGAACCUAAUUUUCUAUUUCUCUUUUUUUUUUUUUAAUAUUACAUUUUGACUCUUCACCUGGACACAGCCACAUUGAGAUUAAGGUAUUCUCUGAAUUAAAUCUGUUCUGGGUAUUUUGUGAGUACGUUUAGAAUUUCAGGUCAGGUGCAGUGCCUCAUGCCUGUAAUCUCAGCACUUUGGAAGGCUGAGAGAGAAGGAUCGCUUGAGCCCAGGAGUUCAAGACAGUCUCUCUACAAAAUAUAAAAAUAAAUUAAAAAGCCAGGUGCAAUAGUGUGUGCCUGCAGUCCCAGUUACUUGGGAGGCUGAGAUGAGAGGAUCUCCUGAGCCCAGAAGGUCAAGGCUGCAGUGAGCCAUGACCAUGCCACUGCACUUCAACCUGAGUGAAAGAGCAAGUUUUAGAAUUUCUAUCUUGGAAUAGAAGCCAAAUUGGGAACCAAGAGGCGAAUCACUUAAAGUCACCUGACAAAUCAAAAACCAACCUUAAAUCAAGUCGUUUCUCUUUCUUACUUGCUGCAAUGAUAUUUAAAAUAUAUGUUGCCCUGGUUGAGACUGUUUGUCUUGGAUCAACAUCAUUCUAAAGAAAAAGGGUAAAUUUGACAGGGAUGCUUAUUUUACAUUUCUUCCUUUCGCUUUUUCAAGUUUUUACAACUAAAAUAAAUGAAUAGUGUAGCAGCUGGAAUAGAAAUCUCUUACUGAUUGGGCCAUAAAAGUGGGAGCUUUCAGAAACAGCCUAUUCUCCACAAAAUAAAAUAACCUAGACAUUGUCCAAACUGUUCAAUGCUAGACUUGAGAACUAUAGUUUUAAAGCUUCUUUUGCUAUGGAUUUAUUAUCAUUUAUAAAUAUUAUGAAUUUUCAAAUGAGUUAGCAACUAUCAAGACAGGUAAAUCUCACACCCUCUUCUGUGUUCCCACAGCCAUUUUUAUACAUACCUUGUUAUAAUUAUUAUCUUUUUCACCCAGUAGCCUACGGGUUCUUUGAGGGCAGUAUCAGGUCUUGGUUAUCUUUCUCUCUCACAGCACAGUGCCUUGUGUGUGAUAAAGCCCCCAACAAACUGAAUUAAUAAAAACUAUAGAUCAUCCUGCCCAGACUGUUUUAGGAAGUAUUUGUGUAUCUCCUCCCCCUAGUAGUUUGGUUUGGUCAGCUCUGUGCCCAGCAUCUCUGCUCAGAAGGCAAGGACAAGGGAGGGAAGGAGGGACUGAAAUUUCUUUGGCUGACUGACCAGAUGCAGUGGCUCAUGCCUGUAAUCCCAGCACUUUGGGAGGCCAAGGCGGGUUGAUCACUUGAGGUCAGGAGUUUGAGACUAGCCUGGCCAACAUGGUGAAGCCCCGUCUCUACUAAAAAUACAAAAAUUAGCUGGGCGUGCUGGCACAUGCCUGUAAUUCCAGCUACUUGGGAGGCUGAGGCAGGAGAAUUGCUUGAACCAGAGAGGUGGAGGUUGCAGUGAGCUGAGAUCACGCCAUUGCACUCCAGCCUGGGCGAAGAAGCGAGACUCCAUCAAAGGAAAGAAAGAAAAGAAAAGAAAGGAAAGAAAAAGAAAAAGAAGAUAAAAAGAAAGAGAAAGAAAAGAAGAAAAGAUUCCUUUGUCUAUUCUCAUUAGCAGCUCAUUCAGUUCCAUUCAGUGAACACUCUGAGCAUCUGCCUCACUUCAGACCUUGCUCCAGAUGCGGAAUUCGCCAAGAUGAGUGAGAGGGUCUACUUUGGGCAAAGCUCUCUGAGCCUUGAGGUCUGUCUUCAUCCCAAAGAAUUUGCACUCUAGCAGGGGAGAGGGGAAAUGAAUGGACGAAUAUUUAUGUAUUACUUGGGUUGAGGGAGCAGUCAAUUCUUCAGGGAAGGGAGAGCAAGGAAAACAAAGAAGGGAAGUGACAGGGGAAGGGAAGGAGGUUCCAGAAUGCAUCAGGUGGAUAAGUAGCAGUCUUGAAGUGUGAAAAUUAAUACAUGGUAUAUUUGGGGAGACAGCAAGCACUUUAAGGCAUAGUUUCAAGUAGGGUUGGGGCUUAAGUUGUUGAAGUGAGAGGGAUUUUUUUUUUCCUUAAGGCUUUCUACACGAUUUAGAUUGUAAAUCUUUGGAGGAUAGACUGCUAUACCACCAAGCUUUCCUCAGAGAAGGAGAUCAAAAACAUUGGGAGAUUUAAAUGUAAUAAACUAAUACAGAACUAUAAAGUGUGUGUGUGUGUGAGAGUGUGUGUGUGGGCCUGUGCACUUGCUAAUUUCACUUCCCUUUCCUUGUCCUGUCCACUCUCUGGUAUAUAUAAAUAAUGAACUGAUUAAAACACUCACA